GUGUUUGUGAACUGGCGAUGUGAUCGAGGGCACGGGUGCUGGGCUUCCCCCUCAUGGGUAAAACCAGAGCUACUGUAUGCCAGCCGUGGAGGCAUGGACGGCCCCUGAGCUCGGACAGCAGACGGACAGACCGUUGACGCGUUGGCACCGUGGCCAGAGUCCGUUCAAGAAAGGUCGGCAGAGAGGGCUGAGAACGCGGCAGGCACAUCCUCCAAGGGCCCUGCUGGAACCCCUGGAGCAGGAGGAAGCGGUGAUUCUCCAGGCCUUGGUUUCCUCACUGCUUGGAGGAAGAUGAGAAUUCUCAGAGGUCCUUAUGCUGCCCUUUUUGCUGCAGUCUUGACAUCUUAACGUGGAUAGAAAAAGGCCAGGCCGUGCAGCAUCGAAGACAGGAGGAACUGGAGCCUCAUUGGCCGGCCCGGGGCGCCGGCCUCGGGCUUAAAUAGGAGCUCCGGGCUCUGGCUGGGACCCGACCGCUGCCGGCCGCGCUCCCGCUGCUCCUGCCGGGUGAUGGAAAACCCCAGCCCGGCCGCCGCCCUGGGCAAGGCCCUCUGCGCUCUCCUCCUGGCCACUCUCGGCGCCGCCGGCCAGCCUCUUGGGGGAGAGUCCAUCUGUUCCGCCAGAGCCCUGGCCAAAUACAGCAUCACCUUCACGGGCAAGUGGAGCCAGACGGCCUUCCCCAAGCAGUACCCCCUGUUCCGCCCCCCUGCGCAGUGGUCUUCGCUGCUGGGGGCCGCGCAUAGCUCCGACUACAGCAUGUGGAGGAAGAACCAGUACGUCAGUAACGGGCUGCGCGACUUUGCGGAGCGCGGCGAGGCCUGGGCGCUGAUGAAGGAGAUCGAGGCGGCGGGGGAGGCGCUGCAGAGCGUGCACGCGGUGUUUUCGGCGCCCGCCGUCCCCAGCGGCACCGGGCAGACGUCGGCGGAGCUGGAGGUGCAGCGCAGGCACUCGCUGGUCUCGUUUGUGGUGCGCAUCGUGCCCAGCCCCGACUGGUUCGUGGGCGUGGACAGCCUGGACCUGUGCGACGGGGACCGUUGGCGGGAACAGGCGGCGCUGGACCUGUACCCCUACGACGCCGGGACGGACAGCGGCUUCACCUUCUCCUCCCCCAACUUCGCCACCAUCCCGCAGGACACGGUGACCGAGAUAACGUCCUCCUCUCCCAGCCACCCGGCCAACUCCUUCUACUACCCGCGGCUGAAGGCCCUGCCUCCCAUCGCCAGGGUGACACUGGUGCGGCUGCGACAGAGCCCCAGGGCCUUCAUCCCUCCCGCCCCAGUCCUGCCCAGCAGGGACAAUGAGAUUGUAGACAGCGCCUCAGUUCCAGAAACGCCGCUGGACUGCGAGGUCUCCCUGUGGUCGUCCUGGGGACUGUGCGGAGGCCACUGUGGGAGGCUCGGGACCAAGAGCAGGACUCGCUACGUCCGGGUCCAGCCCGCCAACAACGGGAGCCCCUGCCCCGAGCUCGAAGAAGAGGCUGAGUGCGUCCCUGAUAACUGCGUCUAAGACCAGAGCCCCGCAGCCCCUGGGGCCCCCCGGAGCCAUGGGGUGUCGGGGGCUCCUGUGCAGGCUCAUGCUGCAGGCGGCCGAGGGCACAGGGGGUUUCGCGCUGCUCCUGACCGCGGUGAGGCCGCGCCGACCAUCUCUGCACUGAAGGGCCCUCUGGUGGCCGGCACGGGCAUUGGGAAACAGCCUCCUCCUUUCCCAACCUUGCUUCUUAGGGGCCCCCGUGUCCCGUCUGCUCUCAGCCUCCUCCUCCUGCAGGAUAAAGUCAUCCCCAAGGCUCCAGCUACUCUAAAUUAUGUCUCCUUAUAAGUUAUUGCUGCUCCAGGAGAUUGUCCUUCAUCGUCCAGGGGCCUGGCUCCCACGUGGUUGCAGAUACCUCAGACCUGGUGCUCUAGGCUGUGCUGAGCCCACUCUCCCGAGGGCGCAUCCAAGCGGGGGCCACUUGAGAAGUGAAUAAAUGGGGCGGUUUCGGAAGCGUCAGUGUUUCCAUGUUAUGGAUCUCUCUGCGUUUGAAUAAAGACUAUCUCUGUUGCUCACAAA